ACUAUAAAUAGCAGCCACCUCUCCCUGGCAGACAGGGACCCGCAGCUCAGCUACAGCACAGAUCAGCACCAUGAAGCUUCUCACGGGCCUGGUUUUCUGCUCCUUGGUCCUGAGUGUCAGCAGCCGAAGCUUCUUUUCGUUCCUUGGCGAGGCUUUUGAUGGGGCUCGGGACAUGUGGAGAGCCUACUCUGACAUGAGAGAAGCCAAUUACAUCGGCUCAGACAAAUACUUCCAUGCUCGGGGGAACUAUGAUGCUGCCAAAAGGGGACCUGGGGGUGCCUGGGCUGCAGAAGUGAUCAGCACAAUGAGGCUUUUCACAGGCAUUGUUUUCUGCUCCUUGGUCAUGGGAGUCACCAGUGAAAGCUGGCGUUCGUUUUUCAAGGAGGCUCUCCAAGGGGUUGGGGACAUGGGCAGAGCCUAUUGGGACAUAAUGAUAUCCAAUCACCAAAAUUCAAACAGAUAUCUCUAUGCUCGGGGAAACUAUGAUGCUGCCCAAAGAGGACCUGGGGGUGUCUGGGCUGCUAAACUCAUCAGCCGUUCCAGGGUCUAUCUUCAGGGAUUAAUAGACUGCUAUUUAUUUGGAAACAGCAGCACUGUAUUGGAGGACUCGAAGUCCAACGAGAAAGCUGAGGAAUGGGGCCGGAGUGGCAAAGACCCCGACCGCUUCAGACCUGACGGCCUGCCUAAGAAAUACUGAGCUUCCUGCUCCUCUGCUCUCAGGGAAACUGGGCUGUGAGCCACACACUUCUCCCCCCAGACAGGGACACAGGGUCACUGAGCUUUGUGUCCCCAGGAACUGGUAUAGGGCACCUAGAGGUGUUCAAUAAAUGUUUGUCAAAUUGAA